AUGUUUGACAGCUCGCAGUAUCCCUACAACUGCUUCAAUUACGACGCCGACGACUACCCCGCCGGCAGCUCCGACGAAGACAAGAGGCUCACGCGGCCCGCGUACAGCUACAUCGCCUUGAUCGCCAUGGCCAUUCAGCAGAGCCCCGCGGGGAGGGUGACCCUGUCCGGCAUCUACGACUUCAUCAUGCGCAAAUUCCCCUAUUACCGCGCCAACCAGCGCGCCUGGCAGAACUCCAUCCGCCACAACCUGUCCCUCAACAGCUGCUUCGUCAAGGUGCCGCGGUCCGAGGGCCACGAGAAGGGCAAAGGCAACUACUGGACGUUCGCGGGCGGCUGCGAGUCGCUGCUGGACCUCUUCGAGAACGGCAACUACCGGCGGCGGCGGCGGCGGCGCGGCCCCAAGCGCGAGGGGCCGAGGGGUCCGCGCGCGGGGGGCGCCCAGGGGCCGUCGGGUCCGUCCGAGCCGCCCGCCGCUCAGGGGCGCCUGGCCCCGGACAGCGCUGGCGAGGGCGCCCCGGGCCGUGAGCCCCCCGCCAGCCCCGCUCCCCCGGGGAAGGAGCACCCCCGGGACCUCAAGUUCAGCAUCGACUACAUCCUGUCCUCCCCAGACCCCUUCCCUGGGCUCAAGCCGCCCUGCCUCGCACAAGAGGGCAGAUACCCGCGGCUGGAGAACGUGGGACUCCACUUUUGGACAAUGUGA